ACAGGCAUGAACCACGAUGCUCAGCCCCUUAGCUGAACUUUUAAACAGAGAUUUCUUCUAUUUCAGACAGACACUGAGACUGAGGCACCCAUUCCAUGGAUACCUCCACCAGUGUUACCUAUGACUCCAGCCUCCAGAUUUCCCAGUUCAUCCUGAUGGGAUUACCAGGCAUUCAUGAGUGGCAGCACUGGCUCUCCCUGCCCCUGACUCUGCUCUACCUCUUAGCUCUUGGUGCCAAUCUCCUCAUCAUAAUCACCAUUCAACAUGAGACCGUGCUACAUGAACCCAUGUACCAUUUGCUGGGCAUAUUAGCAGUGGUGGACAUUGGCCUGGCCACCACCAUCAUGCCCAAGAUCCUGGCCAUCUUCUGGUUUGAUGCCAAGGCCAUUAGCCUCCCCAUGUGUUUUGCUCAGAUCUAUGCCAUCCACUGCUUCUUCUGCAUAGAGUCAGGCAUCUUUCUCUGCAUGGCAGUAGACAGAUACAUAGCCAUCUGUCGCCCUCUUCAGUACCCCUCCAUAGUCACUAAAGCUUUUGUCUUCAAAGCCACAGGGUUCAUCAUGCUCAGGAAUGGCCUGUUGACCAUCCCAGUGCCUAUACUGGCUGCCCAGAGACACUACUGUUCCAGGAAUGAAAUCGAGCACUGCCUCUGCUCUAACUUGGGGGUUAUCAGCCUGGCUUGUGAUGACAUCACUGUGAACAAAUUUUACCAACUGAUGCUAGCAUGGGUCUUGGUUGGGAGUGAUAUGGCUCUGGUAUUUUCUUCCUAUGCUGUAAUCCUUCACUCUGUGCUGAGGCUGAACUCAGCAGAAGCAAUGUCCAAGGCUCUGAGCACUUGUAGCUCCCACCUCAUCCUCAUCCUCUUCCACACAGGUAUCAUUGUGCUGUCUGUCACACACCUUGCAGAGAAAAAGAUUCCCCUUAUUCCUGUGUUCCUUAAUGUGCUGCACAAUGUCAUCCCCCCUGCACUCAACCCCCUGGCCUGUGCACUCAGGAUGCACAAACUCAGACUGGGCUUUCAGAGACUGCUUGGACUGGGUCAGGACGUGUCCAAGUAACUCCAGCUUUAGGAAUCCAGUAAGAUGUUAGGAAAUGACAGAGGUUUUAGUUCUCAAUAGAUCAGGGUUAUAAUCUGCACUUACCACACUCCCUAGG